ACACUUGGACAGCAAACUGAUUUCAAACCACUCCUUUUCAAAGAUCUCUGAGGGAGACAUUGCACCUGGCCACUGCAGCCCAGAGCAGGUCUGGCCACGGCCAUGAGCAUGCUGAGCCAUCAUGCCCACCGUGGAUGACAUUCUGGAGCAGGUUGGGGAGUCUGGCUGGUUCCAGAAGCAAGCCUUCCUCAUCUUAUGCCUGCUGUCGGCUGCCUUUGCGCCCAUCUGUGUGGGCAUCGUCUUCCUGGGUUUCACACCUGACCACCACUGCCAGAGUCCUGGGGUGGCUGAGCUGAGCCAGCGCUGUGGCUGGAGCCCUGCGGAGGAGCUGAACUAUACAGUGCCAGGCCUGGGGCCCGCGGGCGAGGCCUUCCUUGGCCAGUGCAGGCGCUAUGAAGUGGACUGGAACCAGAGCGCCCUCAGCUGUGUAGACCCCCUGGCUAGCCUGGCCACCAACAGGAGCCACCUGCCGCUGGGUCCCUGCCAGGAUGGCUGGGUGUAUGACACGCCCGGCUCUUCCAUCGUCACUGAGUUCAACCUGGUGUGUGCUGACUCCUGGAAGCUGGACCUCUUUCAGUCCUGUUUGAAUGCGGGCUUCUUGUUUGGCUCUCUCGGUGUUGGCUACUUUGCAGACAGGUUUGGCCGUAAGCUGUGUCUCCUGGGAACUGUGCUGGUCAACGCGGUGUCGGGCGUGCUCAUGGCCUUCUCGCCCAACUACAUGUCCAUGCUGCUCUUCCGCCUGCUGCAGGGCCUGGUCAGCAAGGGCAACUGGAUGGCUGGCUACACCCUAAUCACAGAAUUUGUUGGCUCGGGCUCCAGAAGAACGGUGGCGAUCAUGUACCAGAUGGCCUUCACGGUGGGGCUGGUGGCGCUUACCGGGCUGGCCUACGCCCUGCCUCACUGGCGCUGGCUGCAGCUGGCAGUCUCCCUGCCCACCUUCCUCUUCCUGCUCUACUACUGGUGUGUGCCGGAGUCCCCUCGGUGGCUGUUAUCACAAAAAAGAAACACUGAAGCAAUAAAGAUAAUGGACCACAUCGCUCAAAAGAAUGGGAAGUUGCCUCCUGCUGAUUUAAAGAUGCUUUCCCUCGAAGAGGAUGUCACCGAAAAGCUGAGCCCUUCAUUUGCAGACCUGUUCCGCACGCCGCGCCUGAGGAAGCGCACCUUCAUCCUGAUGUACCUGUGGUUCACGGACUCUGUGCUCUAUCAGGGGCUCAUCCUGCACAUGGGCGCCACCAGCGGGAACCUCUACCUGGAUUUCCUUUACUCCGCUCUGGUCGAAAUCCCGGGGGCCUUCAUAGCCCUCAUCACCAUUGACCGCGUGGGCCGCAUCUACCCCAUGGCCAUGUCAAAUUUGUUGGCGGGGGCAGCCUGCCUCGUCAUGAUUUUUAUCUCACCUGACCUGCACUGGUUAAACAUCAUAAUCAUGUGUGUUGGCCGAAUGGGAAUCACCAUUGCAAUACAAAUGAUCUGCCUGGUGAAUGCUGAGCUGUACCCCACAUUCGUCAGGAACCUCGGAGUGAUGGUGUGUUCCUCCCUGUGUGACAUAGGUGGGAUAAUCACCCCCUUCAUAGUCUUCAGGCUGAGGGAGGUCUGGCAAGCCUUGCCCCUCAUUUUGUUUGGCCAGAGAACUUCCAAGACCCUGCUUACCCACUUGAUAGAAGACAACAGUUGCUGGUUGUUUGCAGAGCCAGCCAUGCCUGGGCACAGCGGUGUUGGGCCUGCUUGCCGCGGGAGUGACGCUACUUCUUCCAGAGACCAAGGGGGUCGCUUUGCCAGAGACCAUGAAGGACGCCGAGAACCUUGGGAGAAAAGCAAAGCCCAAAGAAAACACGAUUUACCUUAAGGUCCAAACCUCAGAACCCUCGGGCACCUGAGAGAGAUGUUUUGCGGCGAUGUCGUGUUGGAGGGAUGAAGAUGGAGUUAUCCUCUGCAGAAAUUCCUAGACGCCUUCACUUCUCUGUAUUCUUCCUCAUACUUGCCUACCCCCAAAUUAAUAUCAGUCCUAAAGAA